GAGGUCAGAGACUUAAGUCUAAGGCACUGAGCGUAUCAUGUUAAAGAUGAGCGGGUGGCAGCGACAGAGCCAAAAUCAGAGCUGGAACCUGAGGAGAGAGUGUUCAAGAAGGAAGUGUAUCUUCAUACAUCACCACACCUGAAAGCAGGUAAACUUAACCUACCCUUUUCCAAAAAUUUUAAACGGCAGGACAGUAAAUAUUUUAGAUGUUAAAAGUCCUAUAGUCUCUAGCGUGACUCUUCAUCUCUGCCACUGUAGCACCAAAGCAGCCAUAAACAAUAUGUAAAUAAACAGAUGUGGCUGUAUUCCAGUACAACUUUACCUACAAAAACAGGCAUCAGACCAGCUUGCCAACUUGUGGCAUAGACUGUUUGCUACAUGGAGCUUGUUCCAGCCACUCCCCAUUAUCCUGCAGAUGUGCUUUUCCAGACUGAUCCAACUGCAGAGAUGGCAGCUGAGUCAUUGCCUUUCUCCUUCGGGACACUGUCCAGCUGGGAGCUGGAAGCCUGGUAUGAGGACCUGCAAGAGGUCCUGUCUUCAGAUGAAAAUGGGGGUACCUAUGUUUCACCUCCUGGAAAUGAAGAGGAAGAAUCAAAAAUCUUCACCACUCUUGACCCUGCUUCUCUGGCUUGGCUGACUGAGGAGGAGCCAGAACCAGCAGAGGUCACAAGCACCUCCCAGAGCCCUCACUCUCCAGAUUCCAGUCAGAGCUCCCUGGCUCAGGAGGAAGAGGAGGAAGACCAAGGGAGAACCAGGAAACGGAAACAGAGUGGUCAUUCCCCAGCCCGGGCUGGAAAGCAGCGCAUGAAGGAGAAAGAACAGGAGAAUGAAAGGAAAGUGGCACAGCUAGCUGAAGAGAAUGAACGGCUCAAGCAGGAAAUCGAGCGCCUGACCAGGGAAGUAGAGGCGACUCGCCGAGCUCUGAUUGACCGAAUGGUGAAUCUGCACCAAGCAUGAACAAUUGGGAGCAUCAGUCCCCCACUUGGGCCACACUACCCACCUUUCCCAGAAGUGGCUACUGACUACCCUCUCACUAGUGCCAAUGAUGUGACCCUCAAUCCCACAUACGCAGGGGGAAGGCUUGGAGUAGACAAAAGGAAAGGUCUCAGCUUGUAUAUAGAGAUUGUACAUUUAUUUAUUACUGUCCCUAUCUAUUAAAGUGACUUUCUAUGAGCCAA